AAUGCUAAUUUAUUUCACAGGUAUGAUAGUAACCAAAACUCAGGUAACAACCAUUAGCUUUUGCAAGAAGUCAGGUUGACUAGCAAGGAGUCUGCUUCUGCUACUUGGAGAAGAGAUUUAGAAUUAUGUAUCUUUUGUUACAGAUAUACAGAUAUACAAAUAUACAGAUAUACAAAUAAGGGUGAAGAUGGAGGGAAUCUGAUAAAGACAUCUUAUAAAUUCAACAGACACAAAAGAAUUUGAUCUCCCAUAAGCAACUGUGAAAUUACAAUAACAGAUCCUGGGAAGUUCUACAAUUCUAAUUCAGUUUUUUCAAGGGGGAACAUGGCAAAGGUGUUCAGUUUCAUCCUUGUUACCACCGCUCUGACAAUGGGCAGGGAAAUUUCGGCGCUCGAGGACUGUGCCCAGGAGCAGAUGCGGCUCAGAGCCCAGGUGCGCCUGCUUGAGACCCGGGUCAAACAGCAACAGGUCAAGAUCAAGCAGCUUUUGCAGGAGAAUGAAGUCCAGUUCCUUGAUAAAGGAGAUGAGAAUACUGUCAUUGAUCUUGGAAGCAAGAGGCAGUAUGCAGAUUGUUCAGAGAUUUUCAAUGAUGGGUAUAAGCUCAGUGGAUUUUACAAAAUCAAACCUCUCCAGAGCCCAGCAGAAUUUUCUGUUUAUUGUGACAUGUCCGAUGGAGGAGGAUGGACUGUAAUUCAGAGACGAUCUGAUGGCAGUGAAAACUUUAACAGAGGAUGGAAAGACUAUGAAAAUGGCUUUGGAAAUUUUGUCCAAAAACAUGGUGAAUAUUGGCUGGGCAAUAAAAAUCUUCACUUCUUGACCACUCAAGAAGACUACACUUUAAAAAUCGACCUUGCAGAUUUUGAAAAAAAUAGCCGUUAUGCACAAUAUAAGAAUUUCAAAGUUGGAGAUGAAAAGAAUUUCUACGAGUUGAAUAUUGGGGAAUAUUCUGGAACAGCUGGAGAUUCCCUUGCGGGGAAUUUUCAUCCUGAGGUGCAGUGGUGGGCUAGUCACCAAAGAAUGAAAUUCAGCACGUGGGACAGAGAUCAUGACAACUAUGAAGGGAACUGCGCAGAAGAAGAUCAGUCUGGCUGGUGGUUUAACAGGUGUCACUCUGCAAACCUGAAUGGUGUAUACUACAGCGGCCCCUACACGGCUAAAACAGACAAUGGGAUUGUCUGGUACACCUGGCAUGGGUGGUGGUAUUCUCUGAAAUCUGUGGUUAUGAAAAUUAGGCCAAAUGAUUUUAUUCCAAAUGUAAUUUAAUUGCUGCUGUUGGGCUUUCGUUUCUGCAAUUCAGCUUUGUUUAAAGUGAUUUGAAAAAUACUCAUUCUGAACAUAUCCAUGCGCAAUCAUGAUAACUGUUGUGAGUAGUGCUUUUCAUUCUUCUCACUUGCCUUUGUUACUUAAUGUGCUUUCAGUACAGCAGAUAUGCAAUAUUCACCAAAUAAAUGUAGACUGUGUUAA